CCGGAGGCCCCAGGCAGGGCCCAUGCCAGGUUGUAAUCUGCUGCUGCCUGCUGCCCCACCCCACUCUUCUUCUCUGGCUUCCACUUCCUGGUGGGCAGCCUGUGGUGCCUGCUGCCUAACAGAAUACCACGGUGGUAGUGGAUUCCCGCAGGUGCUUGGGAGUGGGAUUCAUUUGCUCUCAUGUUUGGCUUCAAGUUUUAUGCGAUUUCUUAGGUGAGGGAUGUGGGGAGAGGUGGUCAUGCUGAGGGGCUAUAUGUGUGUCCUAGCCAUGAAGGGGUCCCCCACUCUUAAGGACGUGAGGCAUGAGGAUGCACUAAGGGGAAAGUGGUGGAGGAGAAGGGCGCUGGCAGGGUGGCCCUGCCAGCUGACUCGGAGGGAUGUGUGUGCUGGGCGACGGCAUUUGCACAUGCAGAAUGGAAUGAUGGAAUGGCCGUGAGGGGUGCUGUGUCUGACUGAGAGGCUGAUGGUGAGGGAUUGGAGGGUGAGGAUGAUGGCCAAGGAGGGUGUGUGUGCGUGCACGUUUGCACGUGUACAUUUGUGGAUUGACUGAAGGAUGUCCUUGCUGUCUCUGAGGGACCAGGCCUGGCCUAGAAGGGACACAGACUGUUUUUAGGUUGUGCUGUCAGGCCGUGGGGGUGCUGUCAGGGAUCUGAAUGUGAAGGCACGAGGGGUGAGUGCACCAUCCCACCUGAUGGUGACAAGUGACUGAUUUUGAGGUGGCGAUGGCUGGAGGGCACCUGCUGCCUUCCUGCCCCAGGCCACCUGUCAGGCAAGGAGCGGGUGGCUGAGUACCCCUCCUGGGAGAGAAGGAUUGACUGGCAGAGAGGGCAGAUGCUGAGGUGGGGCAGGCGAGGUGUCUGGAAGGUGCUAUUUUCUUAAAAAAUGCCAGGGGACUGCUGGAAAUGGGCUGUGGAGGUGUAGCUUGGCUAGGAACUCCCAGAAAGGAAAGUCAGGAAUGCCACAUGUCCUAGGAUGUGGCUGCAGGGAAUUUCUUCCAGGAUUCUAACAUCCUACACCUGUGGGAGCCCGGCAGGCUGCGAUGUGACACUCACAUCACAGUGGACUUUGCUUCUGGAGGCUUCUGCACAGGGAAUCUUAUCUUGCUCCCUUGGCCGUGUUAGCUCCAUUGCCGGAAGUACAUGAGACAUUGGGCGUCACCACAGGAGCCAAGCCUGUCAACGCCCACCCCGUUCCAAAGCCCUUGUCCCACUCAGGGCUACUCCACUGGGUGUUUGUCAUCCCCAGAGGGGCCUUCUGCCCAGGGAAGAGCCACCUCUGUAGCCUUGGGGAAGUCCAUCCCAUGACCAACCAGAAGAGCAGAGUCUGGUGUAGUUCUACCACUGACAUCAUGGCUGGGGCAGGUCACUCUGCCUCUUGGAACCUCCCUCAGUUUCCUCAUCUGUCAAAUGGGAUCAAUUGUAUCUGCAUGGAACCUGGCUUUUAUGUGCCUCAAAUAGAAUUCACCUUUAUCAAUAUCAUCACCACUGUUGUCAUUGCUACCUUUACCUGGUAGUCACUGAUACCAAGCGCACUCCUAAGUGGCUUUAUGUGGAUCAUAUAUUCAGCAAAUAUUUGCAGAGUACCAACUGUGUGCCAAGCGCUGUUCUAGGCUCUUGGGAUAGAACAGUGAACAGAAUGGUCAUCUCCCUACUCACGUGAGGCCUCUAUUUCAGCAUGAGGAGAAGGAAAAUUUACAACAAAAACGAGCAAAAGGCUCUCUAUUCUGGGAAGGUGACAAGUGCUAAGAGAAAGUGAAGCUGGAAAGGGAGGUGGGCCAUGCUGGGGAAUGGGAACUGAUGUUUCAACUUUAAUUAUCUUGCUUAAUCCUCGCAGCAUCCCCGUGGGAGAGAUAUUAGUCCUAAGUUUCCAGUGAGGAAACUCAGGCACAGAGAUGCUGAUUGACUUCCCUAAGGUUGCACAGCCCAUGGGCAGCAGAGCUGGGAGAAGCAGAGGUCUGUCUGACUUCACAGCAAUGGGACUGGAAGUCACUUUCUCUUGUGAGCCUCCUUUUCUGCAUCUCCAGGUCACGAGAGUGGGACUGACCCUCAUAGUUCUGAGGCUCAGUGAGUCUUUCUUUUAAUUUUACUUUUUUAUUUUUUUGAGACAGAAUCUCACUCUGUCGCCCAGGCUGGAGUGCAGUGGUGAAUCAUAGCUCACUGCAGUUUUGACCUCCUGGGCUCAAGUGAUCCUCCCAUCUCAGCCUCCCAAGUAGCUAGGACUACAGGCACCCCACCAUGCCCAGCUAGUUUUAUUUUAUUUUGUAGAGACAGGGUCUCGCUAUGUUGCCCAGGCUGGUCCUGAACUCCUGGGCUCAAGUGAUCCUCUCGCCUCAGCCUCCCAAAGUACUGGGAUUACAGGCCACCACGCCCAGCUUAUUUUGUUGUUGUUGUUUUGUUUAUUAAUCCCCUUCUAUGCUACAGGGAGUCUUUCUUUGAGUGUAACCUGCAAGGCUGGAACUGCCAGGCCAAACCCCAUUAGCCACUGAAGAAGGGUCAUAGGCCCAUGGAGGGAGGGGGCUCCCCUCUUAGGGGGGAUGGGGAAUGGAGAUAGAUGGUGUCUUUCUAGGUGUGGAAGGCCUCUAGGCCCAAGAAGGGGUAUCUAUGUGGUCACUGUUUCCAUGGAGCAACAUGGGAUGAAUUAGGGGUGAGAGAUACCGCGUGAAGGCCAGUUAGAUUAGCAUGGGGACUUCCCUAUUCUAACCCGUAGAAUCUUAUUCCUCAUUCUUGGCUUUUUUGCCUCCCUGCUUUUUAUUAGAAAGACUUUUUUUCUGAGACAGUGUCUCACUCUGUUGCCUAGGCUAGAGUGCAGUGGUGCAAUCUUGGCUCACUGCAACCUCUGCCUCUUGGGUUCAAGUGAUUGUCCCACCUCAAUCUCCCUAAUAGCUAGAACUUCAAGCACACGCCACCAUGCCUGGCUAAUUUUUUGUUUUUGAUAGAGAUGGAGUUUCAUCAUGUUGCCCAGGCUGGUCUCAAACUCCUGGCUUCAAGUAAUCCACCCCGUUGGCCUCCCAAAGUGUUAGGAUUAGAGGUGUGAGCCACUGUGUCUGGCCGUGAUAUUUUCUGAGUCUCUUCAGUUGUCUGUUAGAACAUUCCACAUUCUAGGGGACCAUGAAUCAGCAGAGGAAGUGGGUUGAGAGCCCAGUACAUAUCCUAAGCAAGGUUGGGCACUAUGAGGGCAUCAGGGUUAAGUAUAAUCUCUCCUGCCCUGGAGCUCACUGCUAAGCUAUGUCACCUCCCCCAGGAAGCCCUCUCUGACACCCUGAUCAGUGAGUUGCUCCUUUUUCAGUGCUCUCCCAGCACCUGACACACAGGUAUGCUGCCCCUUCUGUGCUGCACUGUAAUUAUGUUUGUGUCUCCUGCAUGAGGCUGUGAGGACCCCUAGGGGAGAACAGGAGUUAGUCACACCUCUACCUGCAGGGCCAGGGACUCUGCUGGGGUGUACAAGGUGUGUCCUGCACAAGGAUGCCCAGCCAAGGGGGUGCAUGGGGACUGGAAUCCAGCCCACAUUCCACUUGUCAAACCAUGAGCCCUGGCACUGGGCUGUGUCUGCCAGCAGGAAGUACCUUUUCCUAAUUCACUUAAAGGAAACAUAUGGAUUGCAGCGGGCCUGCUUAGCACUGUACCGGCAUUCAGUUGGCGCUCGGUAAAUGGUUGUUGCUUAUGUGCAUGAUAGAGGGUGGGAAGGGUUGGGGCAGAUGAAAGUCUUCAGAAGAGGUGUGCUGGUGACUAUUCUUUGGUGGGGGCAGGAGACCUGAUUCAUGGCAUUUGCUGAUUCCCAUGGUGCCAAUACUCCCACAGUGGCUGAUGCCAAGCUGCUGGGAUAGGAAGGGGUGUGCACAGUCAGCCCUCACAAGCCCCUAAUAGUGGACUCCAGCUCACCACUGCGGUUUUACAUUUAUGAUCUUAAAACUUCAUCUGAAACAGACUUCGAAGGGGGAGAGAGAGAGAGAGAGAGAGAGAGAGAGAGAGAGAGAGAGAGAGAAUGUACUUCUGUUUGAAGUUUGGGGCCUCCUAAGGAUGAGAGAUUGCUUCAUCCAGUUCUGUGCAACCUGUGCCGUUCCCCUUGGGAAGCUUGCCCAAGGGGAGGCCGUGGAAUGACCCCCUGGAAUGAGCCCAUGAGGCCUAAAGCAGAGCCCUCUAACCACUCCACCCAGCCUGUCUGUGGCCUUCGGCCUCAACAGAGAAUGCCCAGGGGAGAUAUCUAUUCCAUCUCCUGGGCAUGAGCCUUACUAUUCUGCCUCGAUUCCUUCACACACACUGUUUACUGCUUCCAAAUCCUACAUGCCUCCUGCAGAACCUGCACAAGCCCCACCACUUGCAGGAAGCUGCCCUGUCUGUCUGGACAUCAAGUCCUUCUCAUCCCAUAGCUUUAUGGGCCCCAGACUUGUUCCCGCAAAGCAGGCUCAGACUUUAUCCCUUUCAAACCACAGCCUCUCUUUUCCUCACCCCAGGGGCCUCACCUGGAUGAAUCCCCAACCAUCAAAAUCCUUAUCAAUUGACUGAACUAAGACAUUCAGUGACAGGGCCAACGCACCAUGGAGACUGGACAGAGAACAUCUCGAAAAGUCCGGAAGCUGGGCUCCAACCGGCGGCGGCAGACAAGAGAGCCAGCUGAUGGUGAAGGCGCUGCAGUGGCCCCAGAGCCAGAGUCUUGGUCCUCUCAGGCAGCGGCAGAACUGCAGGCCUUCUUCCAGGACUGUGGUGCCAAGGAGAGGGGCUUUGUCACCCGCGAGGACCUGGCGGUGGCCAAGUUCAGCUUCCUGGGCAGCAAGGAAGAGUCAGAGAUGAUCUUCGACUGGGUGGAUGUGGAGCGGAAGGGACACCUGUCCCUUGAAGAAUUCAGCUCUGGACUCAAAAACAUCUUUGGCUCCAGCCAGAGCCCCCACAGGCUCCGCAGAAGGAAGCCACUGCCCUCUAAGCGGGUAUCUGCUACCACCAGCUUCCCAGCUCUGGAGGAGGCGGAUGCUGAGGAGAAGGAGGCGUUCCUUGCCUUCAUGGAGCAGCUGGGGACUGGACACUUACUUCCCAAGCAGAUGGAAAUCUGGCAACUGUGGGGGCAGCUGCGGCAGGAGGAGCCCCAGCUGGCAGGCAACCUGGCAGGCUUUCUGGCCAAGAUGACCAGCCGCCUGCAGGAGGCCCAGGCGGACAAGGAGGCCCUGGAGCUGACCCUGAGGAAGCGUGACUCUGACCACCACCGCGAGGUCCAGCAGCUCUAUGAGGAGAUGGAGCAGCAGAUCCGCCAGGAGAAGCAGCAGCUGCAGGCUGAGAGCGACUCUCGGGGCCUGGCCCUCACCUCCCAGAUGCAGGACGUCCUAGAGGCCAAGGAGCGCGAGGUGCAGCGACUAGCUGAGGGCCAGAGGGAGCUGGAGGCCCAGCUCUCCCACCUCAGGAGCACACAUCAGGAGGCUGCCUCAGAGAACCAGCAGCUGCAGGAGGCCAAGCGUGACCUGGCUGGGCGGCUGGAGGAGGUGCGGGGGCAGCUGCAGGUGACCAGGGGGCGCCUGGACGCCGCCAGGGGCCGGGUGUCCUGGCAGGUGGAGGAGAAACUGAGUUUUCCUGGAGCGGGUGAGAAGACCCCAGACCCUCAGGCUGCCUCCCCUGAGGAGGCCCCCCUGCCUGGGCUAUUUGGGGACAACGAUGACUGGGACCAGCUACUGAGCAACUUUGGCAGCCCUCCGCACGGAGCCCUGCAGCUCUGCUGGAGCCCGCCCCCGACCCCAAGAGCCACCUCAGGCCCCCAGACACCCCGUGUGGUCAGGCAGAUCUCCAUCUCGGAGCCACAGGCUUUUCUAUUUGGUCAGGAGCCAUCUUCAGAUCCAGAUGGGGCUCCAAGGACCCCACCUGGGGUGACUUUCAGCGCCAAGGACAAUAAAGGAGUGGACCCACAUGAGCAGGACAUUAGAGCAGAGCAGCCUGUUGAACCGCACGACCCGGACCCCAACCAGGAGCCAGGGUCCACACCCGAGGGCCGCCUCCUCUGGGGUCUCUCAGGAAGCCUGGUGGCACCUGCAUUCAAAGUGCUCAUUCCUUUGGAGGAUGGGCCCCCUCCCCCUGCGAACUCUCCCCCUCCCCAGGCCCCAGCUGGGUCCAGCAAACAGAUCCAGGCCUCAGACCCAGAUGACAAGGGCCCUGGGUCUUGGGCUCCUCCCAGCGGGGCUCAGCCUGGGGCUGGAGCAGGACCCCAGGAACCCACACAAACCCCUCCCACCAUGACUGAGCGGGAAACCCAGCCCGGACCCUCACCCACAACUGCCCUCACAGGAGUGGGCCCAGCCAAGCCGCCCAGGCAGAGAGAUGCCCUCCAGCAGGACCUGCAUGCCACUGGCUCUGAGCCAAGACUGGGGACCCAGAGGGCUAGAGCCCUCACCCUGGGGCCAGCUGAGCCCUUCCAGGGCCUGGAAUUUGUGGGUCCGGUGCCCACAGAGAGGCUGGAGCAGGGCCAGGCGGGCCCAGCGGUGCAGGAGGGCCUUCCUGAGGGGCUAAGAGAAGCUCAUGGCCAGGUCCUUGGGCUGGGUGAGCUGUCUGCCUUCCCCCACCAGGAGCUGGAAGAGGAACCCAGGUCUGAGGAAGGAAAACAAGAGGGCAGAGGUGGGCAGGACCUCAGUUCAGAGCAGUCAGAGCAGUCGGUUGAGGCUCACGGCCUAGAAACUGCGCAUUCGGAACUCCCCCAGCAAGACUCUCUGCUUGUUUCUCUCCCAUCUGCCACACCACAGGCUCAGGUGGAAGCAGAAGGCCCCACUCCUGGAAAAUCGGCACCUCCAAGGGGCUCUCCUCCCAGGGGGGCUCAGCCUGGGGCUGGAGCAGGACCCCAGGAACCCACGCAAACCCCUCCCACCAUGGCUGAGCAGGAAGCCCAACCCAGGCCAUCCCUCACGACUGCUCACGCAGAAGAACAAGGCCCGCCUCACUCCAGGGAACCAAGGGCAGAGAGCAGGCUUGAAGAUCCAGGAAUGGACUCCAGGGAAGCUGGGCUGACCCCAUCCCCGGGAGACCCCAUGGCUGGAGGGGGACCCCAGGCCAACCCUGAUUACCUCUUCCAUGUCAUCUUUCUGGGAGACUCCAACGUGGGCAAAACAUCCUUCCUGCACCUGCUGCACCAGAAUUCUUUCGCCACCGGAUUGACAGCUACCGUGGGAGUAGAUUUUCGGGUCAAAACCUUGCUGGUGGACAACAAGUGCUUUGUGCUGCAGCUCUGGGACACAGCUGGCCAAGAGAGGUACCACAGUAUGACGCGACAGCUGCUCCGCAAGGCUGACGGGGUGGUGCUCAUGUACGACAUCACCUCCCAGGAGAGCUUUGCCCACGUGCGCUACUGGCUAGACUGUCUCCAGGAUGCAGGGUCGGAUGGGGUGGUCAUCCUUCUCCUGGGAAACAAGAUGGACUGUGAGGAGGAACGGCAAGUGUCCGUGGAAGCUGGGCAGCAACUGGCCCAGGAACUGGGGGUCUAUUUUGGGGAGUGCAGUGCCGCCUUGGGUCACAACAUCCUGGAGCCUGUAGUAAACCUGGCCAGGUCACUCAGGAUGCAAGAAGAAGGCCUGAAGGACUCGCUGGUGAAGGUGGCCCCCAAGAGGCCGCCCAAGAGAUUCGGCUGUUGCUCCUGAUCACCUGUCCUGUCCUGGGUAGGAUGGACACCCAUGGGGUUUCCUGUCCCUCAGCUCCUGUCCUUUGUUCCUGGACAGCAACGACACAGAGGACCAGCUUGGAGGUUCAGGAAAACCCUUCUCAACUCAGGACUCGGAUCCCAGAGCAGGGCCGCAUCACCUCUGCCUUUCACACUCCAAAGGAGGGCUUUGCUGAGUGAACAAGGCUUGAGGGGCAGGGGUAUGGCAAAACUCUCCAAACAAAGAAAGUCUAGAAAAACGACUUAAGGAAAAUACACCAAAAUAUUGGCCGCACAUCUGUGGGUGUAAAAUUUUAGGGAGAAUGUGGGGGGGGGGUGUUACUUUCCAUUUUACACAUAUUUGUAUUUUCAGAUUUUCAACAAUAACAGUAUUCAAUACAUAAUCAGAAAAAAGAGAUGUGGAGGAGGAGGAGAGAAACUUCCCAAGGAGCUCCCUUGGGUGCUGCUGGCUCCUAAUUAGUGUAACCUGUUAAUCACAUGUUGCUCGGUGUUAGAGCGGUCCCUCUGUGCUCUGCUUGGCAGGGCGCUGUUGGCCUGGUCUCCCUCGCUAUUUCUAUUUGCAAGCAUGGGCUUUCUUCCCAGCAGAAUCUGGUUCCUGGGAAGAGUAAUGUUCCAAAGGCCUCUGAUAUGCCUCGAUGCCCUCCUGUCUUCCAGAGCCCCAACCUCACUCCCUUUCCCCACCAUACAAAACACACCUCCCAGGGGUCACAUUUGGGGGUCCCGCCCCCUGCUCCAAUGCCAUGGUGUCCCCAAGCACAGGGCUUUGGCCUGAGUUGUCAGUCUCUGGAUGCAUUUGAGGGGCAGCUAGGGUGUGGCUGGGGGGUCCAAGCAGCUGGGGAGCCGAGACUCAGAAUCAUUCACACACUUCUAUUUGGAGCUUUUGUGGAAGUUUCCAGAAUUCCAUAAUAUUCACCUCCUGAAUGGUGGCUGCCCCUUAUCAGCUAGGGCUGGGGUUUCCAGUGCCCUCGGAGAGCUUGCUUUAGAGUCUUGGAGAGACGGCCAUGGUCUUCGUUUGUAUGUCUGUCACAUCUUACCAUCAUCACAAAUUGAAUAUACAACAUGUGCCAGGCA